AUCCUGCCUUCAGAGUCUUACUGCGCGGGGCCCCAGUCUCCAGUCCCGCCCAGGCGCCUUUGCAGGCUGCGGUGGGAUUUCGUUUUGCCUCCGGUUGGGGCUGCUGUUUCUCUUCGCCGACGUGGAUCCUCUAUCCUUCAGAGACUCUGGAACCCCUGUGGUCUUCUCUUCAUCUAAUGACCCUGAGGGGAUGGAGUUUUCAAGUCCUUCCAGAGAGGAAUGUCCCAAGCCUUUGAGUAGGGUAAGCAUCAUGGCUGGCAGCCUCACAGGAUUGCUUCUACUUCAGGCAGUGUCGUGGGCAUCAGGUGCCCGCCCCUGCAUCCCUAAAAGCUUCGGCUACAGCUCGGUGGUGUGUGUCUGCAAUGCCACAUACUGUGACUCCUUUGACCCCCCGACCUUUCCUGCCCUUGGUACCUUCAGCCGCUAUGAGAGUACACGCAGUGGGCGACGGAUGGAGCUGAGUAUGGGGCCCAUCCAGGCUAAUCACACGGGCACAGGCCUGCUACUGACCCUGCAGCCAGAACAGAAGUUCCAGAAAGUGAAGGGAUUUGGAGGGGCCAUGACAGAUGCUGCUGCUCUCAACAUCCUUGCCCUGUCACCCCCUGCCCAAAAUUUGCUACUUAAAUCGUACUUCUCUGAAGAAGGAAUCGGAUAUAACAUCAUCCGGGUACCCAUGGCCAGCUGUGACUUCUCCAUCCGCACCUACACCUAUGCAGACACCCCUGAUGAUUUCCAGUUGCACAACUUCAGCCUCCCAGAGGAAGAUACCAAGCUCAAGAUACCCCUGAUUCACCGAGCCCUGCAGUUGGCCCAGCGUCCCGUUUCACUCCUUGCCAGCCCCUGGACAUCACCCACUUGGCUCAAGACCAAUGGAGCGGUGAAUGGGAAGGGGUCACUCAAGGGACAGCCCGGAGACAUCUACCACCAGACCUGGGCCAGAUACUUUGUGAAGUUCCUGGAUGCCUAUGCUGAGCACAAGUUACAGUUCUGGGCAGUGACAGCUGAAAAUGAGCCUUCUGCUGGGCUGUUGAGUGGAUACCCCUUCCAGUGCCUGGGCUUCACCCCUGAACAUCAGCGAGACUUCAUUGCCCGUGACCUAGGUCCUACCCUCGCCAACAGUACUCACCACAAUGUCCGCCUACUCAUGCUGGAUGACCAACGCUUGCUGCUGCCCCACUGGGCAAAGGUGGUACUGACAGACCCAGAAGCAGCUAAAUAUGUUCAUGGCAUUGCUGUACAUUGGUACCUGGACUUUCUGGCUCCAGCCAAAGCCACCCUAGGGGAGACACACCGCCUGUUCCCCAACACCAUGCUCUUUGCCUCAGAGGCCUGUGUGGGCUCCAAGUUCUGGGAGCAGAGUGUGCGGCUAGGCUCCUGGGAUCGAGGGAUGCAGUACAGCCACAGCAUCAUCACGAACCUCCUGUACCAUGUGGUCGGCUGGACCGACUGGAACCUUGCCCUGAACCCCGAAGGAGGACCCAAUUGGGUGCGUAACUUUGUCGACAGUCCCAUCAUUGUAGACAUCACCAAGGACACGUUUUACAAACAGCCCAUGUUCUACCACCUUGGCCACUUCAGCAAGUUCAUUCCUGAGGGCUCCCAGAGAGUGGGGCUGGUUGCCAGUCAGAAGAACGACCUGGACGCAGUGGCACUGAUGCAUCCCGAUGGCUCUGCUGUUGUGGUCGUGCUAAACCGCUCCUCUAAGGAUGUGCCUCUUACCAUCAAGGAUCCUGCUGUGGGCUUCCUGGAGACAAUCUCACCUGGCUACUCCAUUCACACCUACCUGUGGCGUCGCCAGUGAUGGAGCAGAUACUCAAGGAGGCACUGGGCUCAGCCUGGGCAUUAAAGGGACAGAGUCAGCUCACACGCUGUCUGUGACUAAAGAGGGCACAGCAGGGCCAGUGUGAGCUUACAGCGACGUAAGCCCAGGGGCAAUGGUUUGGGUGACUCACUUUCCCCUCUAGGUGGUGCCAGGGGCUGGAGGCCCCUAGAAAAAGAUCAGUAAGCCCCAGUGUCCCCCCAGCCCCCAUGCUUAUGUGAACAUGCGCUGUGUGCUGCUUGCUUUGGAAACUGGGCCUGGGUCCAGGCCUAGGGUGAGCUCACUGUCCGUACAAACACAAGAUCAGGGCUGAGGGUAAGGAAAAGAAGAGACUAGGAAAGCUGGGCCCAAAACUGGAGACUGUUUGUCUUUCCUGGAGAUGCAGAACUGGGCCCGUGGAGCAGCAGUGUCAGCAUCAGGGCGGAAGCCUUAAAGCAGCAGCGGGUGUGCCCAGGCACCCAGAUGAUUCCUAUGGCACCAGCCAGGAAAAAUGGCAGCUCUUAAAGGAGAAAAUGUUUGAGCCCA